CUCUGUCGGCGCCUGGCAGUUCAGGUGAACAACAGUAACUUCUCAGAGCUGUUCUCCACUCCUGACUUCUCCCAGCCUCGAGAAUUGAUAACACACUCUUCUGGAUCCCAGCAGUGUCCAGAAGAAGACCAAGGACAGAACAGAGACUAGCUUCGGUGAGAUUGGACAGAUUUUGGGAAAGAUCAUGACGAGCCAUCAACCGCAGCCCCAGGAAGAGCAGAGCCCCCAGCGGAGCACCUCAGGGUACCCCCUCCAGGAGGUGGUGGAUGAUGAAGUGUCGGGACCAUCAGCCCCUGGGGUAGAUCCCAGCCCCCCACGUAGGUCCCUUGGCUGCAAAAGGAAGAGGGAGUGUUUGGAUGAAUCUGAUGAUGAGCCAGAGAAGGAGCUCGCCCCUGAGCCUGAGGAGACCUGGGUGGCGGAGACGCUGUGUGGCCUCAAGAUGAAGGCGAAGCGACGGCGAGUGUCGCUCGUGCUCCCUGAGUACUACGAGGCCUUCAACAGGCUGCUUGCCCCUGGGGUAGAUCCCAGCCCCCCACGUAGGUCCCUUGGCUGCAAAAGGAAGAGGGAGUGUUUGGAUGAAUCUGAUGAUGAGCCAGAGAAGGAGCUCGCCCCUGAGCCUGAGGAGACCUGGGUGGCGGAGACGCUGUGUGGCCUCAAGAUGAAGGCGAAGCGACGGCGAGUGUCGCUCGUGCUCCCUGAGUACUACGAGGCCUUCAACAGGCUGCUUGCCCCUGGGGUAGAUCCCAGCCCCCCACGUAGGUCCCUUGGCUGCAAAAGGAAGAGGGAGUGUUUGGAUGAAUCUGAUGAUGAGCCAGAGAAGGAGCUCGCCCCUGAGCCUGAGGAGACCUGGGUGGCAGAGACGCUGUGUGGCCUCAAGAUGAAGGCGAAGCGACGGCGAGUGUCGCUCGUGCUCCCUGAGUACUACGAGGCCUUCAACAGGCUGCUUGCCCCUGGGGUAGAUCCCAGCCCCCCACGUAGGUCCCUUGGCUGCAAAAGGAAGAGGGAGUGUUUGGAUGAAUCUGAUGAUGAGCCAGAGAAGGAGCUCGCCCCUGAGCCUGAGGAGACCUGGGUGGCGGAGACGCUGUGUGGCCUCAAGAUGAAGGCGAAGCGACGGCGAGUGUCGCUCGUGCUCCCUGAGUACUACGAGGCCUUCAACAGGCUGCUUGCCCCUGGGGUAGAUCCCAGCCCCCCGCGUAGGUCCCUUGGCUGCAAAAGGAAGAGGGAGUGUUUGGAUGAAUCUGAUGAUGAGCCAGAGAAGGAGCUCGCCCCUGAGCCUGAGGAGACCUGGGUGGCGGAGACGCUGUGUGGCCUCAAGAUGAAGGCGAAGCGACGGCGAGUGUCGCUCGUGCUCCCUGAGUACUACGAGGCCUUCAACAGGCUGCUUGAGGAUCCUGUCAUUAAAAGAUUCCUGGCCUGGGACAAAGAUCUGAGGGUGUCAGACAAGUAUCUCCUGGCUAUGGUCAUAGCGUAUUUCAGCCGGGCCGGCCUCCCCUCCUGGCAAUACCAACGCAUUCAUUUCUUCCUGGCUCUCUAUCUGGCCAAUGACAUGGAGGAGGACGACGAGGCCCCCAAACAAAAGAUCUUCUACUUCCUGUACGGGAAGACCCACUCUCACAUACCCUUGCGCCCUAAGCAUUGGUUCCAGUUAUGCCGUCCCAUGAACCCGAGGGCCAGGAAGAACUGCUCUCAGAUAGCCUUGUUCCAGAAGCGUCGGUUCCAGUUCUUCUGUUCCAUGCGCUGCAGGGCUUGGGUUUCCCCGGAGGAGUUGGAGGAGAUCCAGGCUUAUGACCCAGAGCACUGGGUGUGGGCGCGAGAUCGCGCCCACCUUUCCUAGAGCUCCAGGGACCGUGGAGGCCUGAGGUCAUCGGCCUGAGAGAAGAACACCGGACCCAGGGGAGAUGUGGAUUUUCAGCAGGAACUUUAUUCCAGUGCUAAUGGCAGACAUCAGGAAGGAGGAGAGGAGCCAUUUGUGCAGAUCAUCUAGAAGAACCUGGACCAUUCUUGACAGAGCUGAAUACAGUGAUCACGUUGUCCUCCAAGGAGCAGGGGUGGGGUGGGGUACUUCUAGGAGUCCUUGGAGAAAAGUAAGAAACCAGGAGUGUUUCCAGUUCCACCCUUUCCUGCGGCACCACCUCCCUUUUUAUAUUGCUGAAUGCCAACCUCCCUGGGGCGGAACCUGGAGGUCCUGUUUCUUACGGACUUGGUUGCCACAGUCCAGGAGCAUUUGAAGGCACAGUGCAGGGGCUCAGAUUGGCACAGAAUUCUUUGUGAAAUAUGAGUGCCACAGACUGUAACAGAUAGCUUCAUGCACACUAUGCAUUUUAUUGGUUUGUUUGGAAAAUGUUGGCCAUUGAAUCAUUAAUAGGUUUAUUUCAAAUAGUUUGGAAAUUGUUGUACUUUUGAAAACAUGCUGUUCCUGUAGAGUUUUUUGAUGAGAGUUAUAGUUGUUAUAUAUACAUAAAGAUAAUUUUCUUUUCAUUUUUAAGUGAGAAUUCUUUUUAUCCUAAAUCUUUUAUUAUCUUUAAAUUUUUCUCUGUAUUAUUAUAUGUGCUCCUGAAGCGAGCACUCUUUUUAUCUAUGAUACUUCCAUAAUAAUCUCUUCUAUUUAUAGCUAUUGGUAGUUCCCCCAAAUUCUGGUCAUAGAAAUUUUUAUUUGCUGUUUAGGUUUGUGACUGAAUUGUGAGAAUUCAGUUGUGAUUUUUAACAUGUCUUAGAUAUAUAUACUAACAUGUCUAAUAUAUACUAUCUAUUUUAUUGAUUUAUUUCGAAAAAGAUGGGCAAAGAAUUAUUUAAAUAUUAUUUUAUUUAUUUAAAUAUUUAUUAAAUAUAUUUAUUUAUUUAAAUAUUUAUUAAAUAUAUUUAUUUAUUUAAAUGUUAUUACUUUAAAUAUUAUUUUAAAUAUUUUGGAAAUACUGGUAUUUUUGAAUAGAUGCUGUUUCUAUAAAGCUGUGUGAUGGGUAUUAUAACUGUUAUAUACACAUAAAUAUAAUUUUGUUUUCCUUUUUAAGAGAGGAUUCUUUUUAUCCUAAAUCUUUUACCUUUCAAUCUUUGUAUCUAUUACUACAUAUGCUGCUGAAGGGAGCAGACUUUUUAUCUAUGAUACUUAGUUAAUGUAUAUAUUACAUUUAUAGCUAUGUGGUAGUUCCCCUAAAUUCUUGUAAAAAUAAAUUUUUAUUUGAUAUUUA